AGGGACCCGCAGCUCAGCUACAGCACAGAUCAGGUGAGGAGCACACCAAGGAGUGAUUUUUAAAACUUACUCUGUUUUCUCUUUCCCAACAAGAUUAUCAUUUCCUUUAAAAAAAAUAGUUAUCCUGGGGCAUACAGCCAUACCAUUCUGAAGGUGUCUUAUCUCCUCUGAUCUAGAGAGCACCAUGAAGCUUCUCACGGGCCUGGUUUUCUGCUCCUUGGUCCUGGGUGUCAGCAGCCGAAGCUUCUUUUCGUUCCUUGGCGAGGCUUUUGAUGGGGCUCGGGACAUGUGGAGAGCCUACUCUGACAUGAGAGAAGCCAAUUACAUCGGCUCAGACAAAUACUUCCAUGCUCGGGGGAACUAUGAUGCUGCCAAAAGGGGACCUGGGGGUGCCUGGGCUGCAGAAGUGAUCACCGAUGCCAGAGAGAAUAUCCAGAGAUUCUUUGGCCAUGGUGCGGAGGACUCGCUGGCUGAUCAGGCUGCCAAUGAAUGGGGCAGGAGUGGCAAAGACCCCAAUCACUUCCGACCUGCUGGCCUGCCUGAGAAAUACUGAGCUUCCUCUUCACUCUGCUCUCAGGAGAUCUGGCUGUGAGGCCCUCAGGGCAGGGAUACAAAGCGGGGAGAGGGUACACAAUGGGUAUCUAAUAAAUACUUAAGAGGUGGAA